AGUGGUCCUGAUCAAAGUGAGAACAGACAGCAGGGAACAUCACCCUCUUCAGACUGGAGUCAGUGGGAACAGACCCAAGAUGUUGGGGAGGAACACUUGGAAGACCUCAGCUUUCUCCUUCUUGGUUGAGCAGAUGUGGGCCCCUCUCUGGAGUCGUUCGAUGAGGCCAGGGCGAUGGUGUUCUCAGCGUUCCUGUGCAUGGCAAACCAGCAAUAACACUUUGCACCCACUCUGGACGGUCCCGGUCUCCGUGCCAGGGGGCACCCGGCAGUCUCCUAUUAACAUCCAGUGGAGGGACAGCGUCUAUGACCCCCAGCUGAAGCCACUCAGGGUCUCCUAUGAAGCGGCAUCCUGCCUGUACAUCUGGAACACUGGCUACCUCUUCCAGGUGGAAUUUGACGAUGCCACCGAGGCAUCAGGAAUUAGUGGUGGGCCCUUGGAAAACCACUACAGACUGAAGCAAUUUCACUUCCACUGGGGAGCAGUGAACGAGGGGGGCUCAGAGCACACAGUGGACGGCCACGCGUACCCCGCAGAGCUGCAUUUAGUUCACUGGAAUUCUGUGAAAUACCAAAAUUACAAGGAAGCUGUCGUGGGAGAGAAUGGUUUGGCUGUGAUAGGCGUGUUUUUAAAGCUCGGGGCCCAUCAUCAGACGCUGCAGAGGCUGGUGGACAUCUUGCCGGAAAUAAAACAUAAGGACGCGCGGGCGGCCAUGCGCCCCUUCGACCCCUCCACUCUGCUGCCCACCUGCUGGGAUUACUGGACCUACGCGGGCUCGCUCACCACCCCGCCGCUGACCGAGUCGGUCACCUGGAUCAUCCAGAAGGAGCCCGUUGAAGUGGCCCCAAGCCAGGGGGCCCUCUGCACCCACCAACAUCUUUGUCUCCUGAAAAAUGGCCUUUGUCAGUUAUUUUUAAAAACUGGUGCUAAUCCUGAGACACGGAGAUACUCCCGGGAAGCCAUCCGAGCCUGGACACACUGAGAUGAAACCACAAACACGCCGAGAGGAAAAGACAUUGAUUCCAGCCCUCAAAGCAACGGGACAAAAAACAAACAGGAGGCUUCCCUCCCGCCCCAGGGGCAGCGGCCGGUGUCUGCGGCUCUGCGGGAAGGGCUCUCACUGUGACCAGAUUGUGGCUUCUGAUUGUAUUGUAGAAUUUCUGGCCCAGCUUUUAAGGUUCAAGGCUUCCUCCCUUUGCUUUUAUCUUAUUUUCUUGUUUAAUAAAGAUACGCCUGUGUGAGAA